ACAAGGGGAGGGCGCCGGGCUGCACAUGGGCCCCUCGGGGAGGCGAGGCCUGCGGGCGAGCCCUUCUGAGGGCAGGGGGUGAGGGGGCGGCGCCCGCCAGCCAGGACAGCAUCCUGCCGCCGUGACAAGCACGCCUCCGGUUGCCAAAACAACCCAAAAAUGUGCCUCAAAACACGUUCGCAAAGCCCCGGGCCGGCCGGUCGCCUGCCUCUCACCUAGCCCGACCGCCCGACGUCCUACUGCCGAGCGAGGGCGAGCAAGCCAAUGAGUCGCAAUCCCAGCAGCAAUAGCCCAGAAGAGGACACGGUUCCCGUACCGAAGGGUUCAGUACCAGCAGCCCGACCAUCACGCGGCGGGAUGUCUGUGGUUGGCAUUGACCUCGGCUUUCUCAACUGCUACAUUGCUGUCGCGAGAAGUGGCGGCAUCGAGACCAUCGCCAAUGAGUACAGCGACAGGUGUACCCCGGCCUGUAUAUCAUUGGGAUCAAGAACUCGAGCCAUUGGAAAUGCAGCAAAGAGCCAGAUAGUCACGAACGUAAGAAAUACAAUUCAUGGCUUCAAAAAGCUUCAUGGGCGAUCAUUUGAUGAUCCCAUUGUGCAAACUGAAAGGAUCAGGCUUCCCUAUGAACUGCAGAAAAUGCCUAAUGGAAGUGCAGGAGUUAAGGUGCGGUACUUAGAGGAAGAGAGACCUUUUGCAAUUGAGCAAGUUACUGGAAUGCUGUUAGCCAAGCUUAAAGAGACUUCAGAAAAUGCUUUGAAGAAACCAGUGGCUGACUGUGUGAUUUCAAUUCCUAGCUUUUUUACUGAUGCCGAGAGAAGAUCUGUGAUGGCUGCAGCCCAGGUUGCAGGCUUAAAUUGUUUAAGGUUGAUGAAUGAAACUACUGCAGUUGCACUGGCGUAUGGAAUUUAUAAACAGGAUCUUCCCCCAUUAGAUGAGAAACCAAGAAAUGUAGUAUUUAUUGAUAUGGGACAUUCUGCCUAUCAGGUCUUGGUUUGUGCUUUUAACAAAGGAAAACUUAAAGUCUUGGCUACUACCUUUGAUCCAUAUUUGGGUGGCAGGAACUUUGAUGAGGCUUUAGUAGACUACUUCUGUGAUGAGUUCAAGACCAAAUAUAAGAUAAAUGUGAAAGAAAACUCUCGGGCCUUGUUGCGUUUAUAUCAGGAAUGUGAAAAACUAAAGAAGCUAAUGAGUGCAAAUGCAUCAGAUCUUCCAUUGAACAUUGAGUGUUUCAUGAAUGACCUUGAUGUUUCUAGUAAAAUGAACAGGGCUCAAUUUGAACAACUGUGUGCUUCCCUUUUGGCCAGGGUUGAACCACCUUUAAAAGCAGUAAUGGAACAAGCUAACUUACAACGUGAAGACAUUAGUAGUAUAGAAAUUGUAGGAGGAGCAACACGAAUUCCUGCAGUGAAAGAACAAAUCACUAAAUUCUUUCUUAAAGACAUAAGUACCACAUUAAAUGCUGAUGAAGCUGUUGCAAGAGGAUGUGCGUUACAGUGUGCGAUUCUCUCACCAGCAUUUAAAGUGCGUGAAUUUUCCAUAACAGACCUUGUUCCCUAUUCAAUCACAUUAAGGUGGAAGACCUCUUUUGAAGAUGGAAGUGGGGAAUGUGAAGUUUUCUGUAAGAACCAUCCUGCCCCAUUCUCAAAAGUCAUUACUUUCCACAAGAAGGAACCAUUUGAACUAGAAGCAUUUUAUACUAAUUUACAUGAAGUGCCUUAUCCUGAUGCAAGAAUUGGGAGCUUCACUAUUCAGAAUGUUUUUCCACAGUCUGAUGGUGAUAGUUCCAAAGUGAAGGUUAAAGUUCGUGUUAACAUCCAUGGAAUCUUCAGUGUGGCUAGCGCAUCAGUAAUUGAGAAGCAAAAUUUGGAAGGCGAUCACAGUGAUGCUCCAAUGGAGACAGAAACUUCAUUUAAAAAUGAAAACAAAGAUAAUAUGGAUAAAAUGCAGGUUGAUCAAGAAGAAGGGCAUCAAAAAUGUCAUGCUGAACACACUCCAGAAGAGGAAAUUGAUCAUACAGGAGCCAAAACAAAGUCAGCUGUCUCAGACAAACAAGACCGAUUAAAUCAGACACUUAAAAAAGGAAAAGUCAAAAGUAUUGAUCUACCGAUCCAGAGUAGCCUAUGUAGACAACUAGGCCAAGAUCUUCUCAACAGCUACAUUGAAAAUGAGGGGAAGAUGAUCAUGCAAGAUAAGUUAGAGAAAGAAAGAAAUGAUGCUAAGAAUGCCGUUGAAGAAUAUGUAUAUGAUUUUAGAGACAGGCUGGGCACUGUCUAUGAAAAAUUCAUCACUCCAGAAGACUUGAGUAAACUGUCUGCAGUAUUGGAAGACACAGAAAAUUGGCUUUAUGAAGACGGAGAGGACCAACCUAAACAAGUUUAUGUGGAUAAGCUUCAAGAACUAAAGAAAUACGGCCAGCCUAUUCAAAUGAAGUACAUGGAGCAUGAAGAGAGACCAAAAGCCUUAAAUGACUUGGGAAAAAAGAUCCAACUUGUCAUGAAAGUGAUAGAAGCUUAUAGAAACAAGGAUGAAAGAUAUGAUCAUCUGGAUCCUACUGAAAUGGAAAAGGUUGAAAAAUGUAUCAGUGAUGCCAUGAGUUGGCUGAAUAGUAAGAUGAAUGCACAGAACAAACUAAGUCUCACUCAAGAUCCUGUGGUAAAAGUUUCAGAAAUAGUAGCAAAGUCAAAGGAACUGGAUAAUUUCUGUAACCCCAUCAUUUACAAGCCCAAACCAAAAGCAGAAGUUCCUGAAGACAAACCAAAAGCUAAUAGUGAACACAAUGGCCCAAUGGAUGGACAGAGUGGAACUGAAACUAAAUCAGAUUCAACAAAAGACAGCUCACAGCAUACUAAAUCCUCUGGAGAGAUGGAAGUGGACUAAGUCUUAAUUUUACCUUCACAUUAAUUCAAACCGUGCAAGUAACCACGGGGUCCAUCUUUUACAUCUGGUACACACAACAGACGCUCAGUUGUUCUUAACCACUUUUGUCAUUUGUUUUUUGGAGUAGUUUUGAAAAGUGUUUUAUAUUGAGUGCACUUCUGUUCAUUUCCAUUGCUGCUUAUAUGCAGUGUUAGCCGAAUUAGAUUUACAAGACAAUCUAAGCUUUCCGGAUAAUUUUAUAUAUCAAACAUACAGGAUGGAUACAUAGUUGGCAACAGUCUACCUUAUUUAAAGCUUCUACUGGGAUAAACCUCAAUUCCUUUAUUCAGGAAAGGAUACUUUAUUGCAUUAUUGUUGCAGAAGCAUAGAUUUAAUUGCAUCUUUAUUUUGAAAAACAAAUGAAAAUUGAUGGGGUUUAAAGCUACAGAGGCACUGACCUUUUUCUAGUUAUUGUAUUGCUACAAUUUAAAUAUUAAAACAAAUAAGAGCUUUCUCAACAAAUUAGUCCAUCUCAUUGAUGUACCACAGAAAUCCAAAGCUUUGCUGUCAUCACAUAAAUGAAUUAAAUCACAUGUGAAAGGGAACACACCCAAUUUUAUGUUAAGGUGAAACCAGCAGUUUGCUUCUUUUAUUAGUAAUGUGGAUUGAUGUUUUCUCAGAGUAACUCGUUGUCUUUUCGCUUGAAAUUUUUGAUCUUGUCCUGAAGACUAGCUGCUGCUAAAACAAUGCUAGCCUAAAGAUACAGGAGUCUCUGACAAAAUGACUUUCAUGUUAAGGGGAAAUGCUGUUUAUCUACUCAGACAUGCAUCUGUGAUGUUCAUAGCCUUGUUUCAGUUAUAAUAGUUGUCUUGUUUUUUUCUUAAUUGAUUUUGUUAAUAAUACCUUAACACAGGGUAGGAAGAAGUGGCACAGUGUAUUGCAUUAUAUACAUUUAUCAUUGAUUUACCUAAUGUUACCUUGUAGAUUAAACACUAUUAAGUGGUAAUACUUGAAAAGGAGCACUUAUACCAUAAGUCUUAGGAAAUAAUGUUUGUAAUAAACUUAACUAUGUUACAUAUCAACAGGCAAAAAUAUAGAAUGUUACAUAGUGUUGUGUGAUUAAAUUAUAGUUCCUGCUGUUAACAUUACCUUUUGAAACCUUGGCUCCAGUUUUGGUGCUUCUUAUACAAAUUAAAUGCGAAAAGGGACUGUAAACUUAAGAUGUAUUUUAAGGACUUUAUCUGUGCUUCAUCACCCAACUUGUUCACAUUGUUAAUUUCUGUCCAGAGACCUGAAACUGCUUAAGUAUGGGAACAGACUGAAAUGGUGUUUCAACCUGCAAGAGACAGAAGCAUAGACAAGUAUAUGAGCCCUUAUGUCCUUAAUGCCAAUCAACUAGAUUGACCUAGGUUAAAAUUUCAAAAGGCUCAUUUUCUCCCAAAGCUAAAUCUUUAUAUUAGGAACAAUUAAAUAUUGACUUAAGUUGUAAAAAUUGAGAGUACAAUAUCUUUAGGGAUAGUCAUUAUUUCUCACAACUAGUUCUCUACGAGAGAUUUUGUUUCUACAAUGUAGUCAGCACUUAAUGGAGAGUAUGGAGUAGUGCAUUUUGCAGGGAUUUUUAUUCCGUCUUUUGAGGGGAAGAAUCUCUUUUUUGCAUUAAAAAAUCAUAUAAACUUAAUAUAUUUUUAAACUCUCCUAGUCUUUAAACUUUCUCUUAAUUCUCUUAAAAUGAAAUAGGUAUAUCCAAUAGGUGAUGAAAUACAUUUUUUACAAACAUAGAUGCUUUUUAUUUGUAUGUUGAAUGUACAGAUUCAUUUCAAGAAAAGCAUGAAGAUAAUGAAAGCAAAUAUGUAACAAUACAAGUAGGGACUUUAGAGCUUCUAUUUGGGUUAAAACAUCCACUCACUUGGUUAGGAGCUAUGCCUCAGAAACUUCCUGGGAGUAAAUAUGGGAACAACUUUUCUAUUAAUACAUCUAAAUUUUCUAGUAUAUCCUGACAUUUUCCAUUCCUGCUCUGAAGUCACUUUUAGUUUUGUGUUUUAGUCAGAUAGUACCACUAAUUUUUGUAAUUAUAUAACACUUCAUUUAAUAACUUAUAUACAUCCAAAUAUAUAUACUUUUUCUACCCAAUUAUUCAACUUAAAAGAUUUCAAAAACGAUUUAGCCUUAUAAUGUAUUUAUUUAUUUAAUUCAUUAAUGAAAGAGAGUGCUCUCUUUAAUGCAGCUUUGGGUAGACAGUCUAAUUCAGUCCAAUUUUAAUCUGCAUUAAAAUAUGCAAUGCUAGACAAAGAUUUUCAAAAUAAAAAGCUAUUAUUUCAGAAAUUAUUUUAAAAGAUGCAUAGUAAAACAGUGUUUUCCUAUGGUAAGCAAAUAAGAAUGAAGUUUGUAGGGAAUAUUUGGAAUGAUUAAUAUAAAUUAGUAUACUUUGGCUCUGUGGAAAAGUGUAAAUUGUGGUUUUAGAAACCAACUCUUGAUAGUUGUACUGUGAUUAUAAAAAACAAUUGUUAAAUAAUAUAAUGGAAGUUUGUGAUAAUUCCUUAGCAGUAAUGUAAAAUUAUUAAGUUUUGGCCAGGCGCUGUGGCUCACGCCUGUAAUCCUAGCACUUUGGGAGGCCAAGGCAGGCAGAUCACCUGAGGUCAGGAGUUCAAGACCAGCCUGGCCAACAUGGUGAAACCCUGUCUCUACUAAAAAUACAAAAAAGUAGCCGGGCGUGGUGGCAUGUCCCUGUAAUCUCAGCUACCCGGGAGGCUCAGGCAGGAGAAUCGCUGGAACCCAGGAGGCAGAGGCUGCCGUUAGCUGAGAUCGUGCUCCUGCACUCCAGCCUGGGCAACAGAACAAGACUCCGUCUCAAAAAAAAAACAAAAAUUCUUCCAAAAAACUAGAAAGAGCACAGCAAAGAAUUUGGCUAUUGAAAUAACAGAUAAACUUGAUUUUGAAAAGGAUAACAAGGCUGGGCACAGUGACUCACACCUGUAAUCCUAGCACUUUGAGAGGCUAAGAAGGGAGGAUCACUUGAACCCAGGAGUUCAAGACCAGCCUGAGAAACAUAGUGAGACCCUGUCUCUAAAAAAAUAAAAACUUAGCAAGGCAUGGUGGUGCACACCUGUAGUCCUAGCUACUCAGGAGGCUGAGGUGGAGGAUCACUUAAGCCUGAGAGGUCAAGGUUGCAAUGAGCCAUAAUCAUACCACUGCACUCCAGCCUGGGCAACAGAGUGAGGCCCUGUCUCAAACACAUAAAAGGCAGUGGCCCACGCCUGUAAUCCCAGCACUUUGGGAGGCCAAGGCGGGCAGAUCACGAGGUCAGGAGAUCAAGACCAUCCUGGCUAACACGGUGAAACCCCGUCUCUACUAAAAAUACAAAAAAUUAGCUGGGCAUGGUGGCGGGCGCCGGUAGUCCCAGCUACUCAGGAGGCUGAGGCAGGAGAAUGGUGUGAACCCAGGAGGCGGAGGUUGCAGUGAGCCGAGAUCGCGCCACUGCACUCCAGCCUGGGCAACAGAGCAAGACUCCAUCUCAAAAACAAAACAAAACAAAAACAUAAAAGGAAAACAAGACAUUUACUAAGAAGAGCUAAAGGAAAGAAUUAAAGGUUUCUUAUGCUUUUUUGGGGGGGGGUGUCAAUUUUUAGUAUAUUAAGAGCUAAAAGAAGUAAAGGUUUCUUAGACUUUUUUUGGGAGGGAGGCGUCAAUUUUUAGUAUAUUUGUGAUUAAUUCCAUGAUAGAAGUCUUUAAAGAGAAUUUUGGGGCUCAAUAAUUUAACAUAAUGUCAGUGUUAAAGCACUUAAUCCAAAUUAGCCCAUCUUUAACUGUUUUGAAAAAUCUAUAUUUAUUAAAGGUAGUAGACAUUUGAAUAUAGUAAUCAAAUUAACUGAUUUUGUUUUCACCCUAAAUACAUACAACCAUUCCUCCACUUUCAUAAAUUUGACAAAUAAUAAGCCUCUCCCAUUAGGAUUUUCUGUUUUAUAGUAAAUAGUUGGUAUUUGGUAGUCCACAAUUAAAGUCAUUGCAUUAAUUUUACAAAUUAUAGAUUUAGAAAUGAUUCUUAAGUUAUUGGUAAAAUAUAACUUUCUCAGUUUUUAAAAGUUUACAAAAUUUUUUUUUUUGUUUUGAGACAGAGUAUGGCUUUGUUACCCAGGCUGGAUUGCAAUGGGGUGAUCUAGGCUCACUGCAGCCUCCACCACCUGAGUUCAAGCGAUUUUUCUGCCUCAACCUCUCCUGAGUAGCUGGGACUACAGGUGCAUGACACCACACCCAGCUAAUUUUUGUAUUUUUAUAGAGAUGGAGUUUUGCCAUGUUGGCCAGCCUGGUCUUGAACUCUUGAACUCCUGACCUCAGGUAAUCCACCCACCUCAGACUCCCAAAGUGCUGGGAUUACAGGCGUGAGCCACCAUACCCGGCCAAAAAUUUUUGCUUUUAAAGUUAAUGUUAUUUUGUGGUUAAACUUCUAAAGUUUUGAACUGUAAGCAGAAUUUUGUUUUGUGAUAUUUUAUUGUAUAAACUGUUAAUGAGAGGCACAGCUAAUUGUACAUAUCAAUAUACAUUUAAAAUCUGGUAACACUGGUUAAAUAGCCCUUGAUGACUUUUCAUGUGGCAUGAGAGGGAUAUGCUUAUAAAGCUUAAUUCUGAUAUUAUCCUCUUACUACCUACAGUAUGUUUUGCAAAAAUCAGUCCACUUAGCAAACUAAUCUUUGUAAAGCAGUCAGUUUCAGAAGAUACUUUUUAUCAAAAAAGAUGGCAGGUUUAACAUUAUACCUUUUGGUUUUUGCCCAACAUUUGAUUUAAUCUAAAGCAAGAAUAUAAAAUAAUUUUAAGAAGCAUAUAAUUUCUUUUGAUAAAAAGUAACAAAAAUUUAAUGCAGAUCAAAGACCAAGGCUUGUAACCAAAACAAGCAAAAAGAAACUUUAGCUGUUUAACUAUCACCUCUCUAAUUUAAAAUGCAUGAAAAUUAAUACUUUGUUUUUGUUUUUUUUUUGGAAACAGUCUCACUCUGUCACCCAGGCUGGAGGGCACAAUCUCUGCUCACUGCAACCUCCACCUCCUGGGCUCAAGCCUCAAGCAAUUCUCCUGCCUCAGCCUCCCAAGUAGCUGGGAUUACAGGAACCCACCACCACGCCCAGCUAAUUUUUGUAUUUUUAGUAGAUGGGGUUUCAUCAUGUUGGCCAGGCUGGUUUUGAACUCCUGACUUCAAAUGAUCCACCCACAUCCACCUGCCAGAGUGCUGAGAUUACAGGCGUGAGCCACCGCACCUGGCCAAUGUUCUUUUAUAUACUCAUGUUUUCUAACAAAACAGCUUUGGAUUUAUAAUGCUGCCAGAUGUCAUUACAAUUUUUUUUCUAAAUUCAAAGGUAAUUAUUCUAAACAAUAAAAGGGCACCUGGAAUUUUCAGAACAUUAAAAAACUGAAACCACUUAGAAGAAAAGAAGAAACCUAAAUGUCUGUGGAAGUGAUCAGUAUUAAGUGGGUGAUGGCUCUUUCAUCUUCCUUAUCCCUAAAGAUACUUCCAACAUAUUGUUAGAGUAAGUAUUAAAAGAAAAAGUAGGUUUGCUGAAAAACAUUACUAAAUGACUUGGAGCUCUCCAGUCAAAGAAACAAAGCUAAUUGAAAUAAUGUACAUUUGGUUCAGUCUGUCAGGCAAGUACAAAUCCAUAACAAAAAAAAUUAAUAGUAUGCUCUUUGCUUUGGAAUCUCUAAUUUACGGUCAUGCCCUAAGUCACAGGAUGAUUAUUAGGGAAAUGUCAUUGACACCUGAAAAUUACCUAUCCUGUAAAAAGACUGGUGAAAUUCAACAUGUUUUAAAUAAUUUAAUUGCAUUAUAGCAUAUAAACUAUAAAUGAAAAUGAUCUUUGUCUUUCCUUUAUCUUGCUUUAUCCUCUUAUCCAAUUCUAGACUCUUAAAUAAUCACUGUAUUUUUCUCAAGUAUUUGUUAUUUUUUAUUAUCCUUUAGAUCUUUUUGUUCAUGGCUCUUUAAAAAUAGUUUUACUGAUAAUCCAAUCACUUGGAUAGUUAAUUUUAUUACUUUUUGUUUCCUUUUUAAUAUUUAUUCUUCCCGUUAAGGGUUUUUUGGCUAUAAAUUCGUACUUGAUAAGCUAUGUUAUUUCUUUGUGUAAUUUAAUAGUAGCAUUCUGGAGUAGAUUCUUUUUUUGUAUUCUGGCCUUGGAAUACUUUAAUUCCGGACCAAAAGAGGUCAAUUUUGUGAGUAUUGCCUAUUAAGUAAACAACAUCCCUCAUUUUUAAUCCAAAUAUCAAUUUGACAGAAUAACAAGGGUCAGAAAUUCAAAAUAGCUGUUAGACACCUUUGAUUCUUUGCUGCUCUCUGGUUAUGUAUGUGUGUUGUGCAUCUUCCUUGUUGUUUUAGAGUUUCCUAAAUUUUUUGCUUCUGGGGACUUGAGUAUUUUUAAAUGUUCUUAAAAUUAUAUGAAUCUACCCAGAAUGUAGAUGUCAAAAUGUAAUUAGAGGCCCCGUGCAGUGGCUCACGCCUGUAAUCCCAGCACUUUGGGAGGCCGAGGCAGGUGGAUCGCCUGAGCUCAGGAGUUCAAGACCAGCCUGGGCAACAUGGCAAAACCCCGUCUCUACUAAAAAUACAAAAAAUUAGCUGGGUGUGGUGGUGUGUGCCUGUAGUCCCAGCUACUCGGGAGGCUGAGGCAGGAGAAUCGCUUGAACCCUGGCGAAACCCCAUUUCUAAAAUAGAAAAAUUUAGCCGGGUGUGGUGGUGUGUGCCUAUAGUCCCAGCUAUUCGGGAGGCUGAGGCAAGAGAAUUGCUUGAACCCGGGAGGUGGAGGUCGCAGUGAGCUGAGAUCCUGCCACUGCACUCCAACCUGGGGGUAACAGAGCGAGACUCUGUCUCAAAAAAAAAAAAAAGUGUAAUUAGAAAUGGAAAUCUAGGUAAAGGAAGCUUUAAAAUGUUGUAUUUUUUCCCUGAAAUAAACUUUUAUGAUUUAAUGUCUUGGAAAAAGACUCACAUGAAAAGUGGCUUUUAUAUUUGGUAGGAUAAAGCCAUUGUCCUUUAAUACCAUAGCAAAUAGAAGCAAUUUUUAAUGAGGUUACUGAAUUGUUUAGUAUUCCUAAUAUGGCAUCCAGGUCAUCUUUUCUUUUCUCCAACCAUUAUUAAAAUAACUUGACACUUUGGGAGGCCAAGCUGGGCAGAUCACCUGAGGUCAGGAGUUUGAGACCAGCCUGGCCAACAUGGUGAAACCCCAUCUCUACUAAAAAAAAUACAAAAAUUAGCGGGGCCAUGGUGACGUGCACCUGUAAUCCCAGCUACUCGGGAGGCUGAGGUGGGAGAAUAGCUUGAACCUGGGAGGCAGAGGUUGUGGUGAGCCAAGAUCACGCCACUGCACUCCAGCCUGGGUGACAGAGCAAGACUCCAUCUCAAGAAAAAAAUAAAUAAAUAAUAAUUUGUGUAUGUGAUGACUGACUCUAGUCAUUAUGGAAAAUAACUUUUGGCAGUUUAGUUCCUAAUGUUAACAAUUCCUCUUUUUAAGAGAGGUACUACAUUUGAUUUCUCAAUUUCUCAGUUUGUUUUCAAUACAAACAGCAACCACUGAAAUGCAGAAAAUGGUAAUCAAGUGUGAUGUUUCUAUAAAAAUAAUUGAGAUUCACAUGUAAUAGACCCUUUAGCUUUAAUGAGCAGACAUGAGAAUGGUUUAUGAUCUUAAGUUGGUAACAUAGGAAUAUGUAUUUGUCAAUUUUAGUUCACAAACAUAUCCAUAAGAAUGUUUACACAUGGCAGUAUCAAAGCAUAUAAAAUAUUUUCUAUGUAAGUAAAUUGCAUCUUUAUGCUAGUGAACAAAGUAGCAAUAAAUGUUCAUUUUUGGAUGGCAGUACACAUUGUUAACAAUCGUGUAAUUAUAAUAAAUAUGUCUACCUACUCCUUGAACCAUGAA